AGCUGAGAACAGAAAGGUUUAGUGCUGACUUGGGUGCUUGGGGUGCGAUGUGUGGGGAGAGGGGGAGUCAGCCUCUCUCCUCAAGCACCCACUCUGGGGUGAGGGGUACAGGGCUGAAGGACAGACUCCAAGUGGCGAGGGAGGGAGACCCCACGCCGUGGGCCAGGCCUCUACAUCAUCCACCCUGGCAGACAUCGCAAAGGGGUCAAAGCACUCGCUGUAGACAUGGGCUCAGUCUCUGCCCCCUGCCCACCCUCAGCGAUGACUACCUGUCCCUGGAGGGUUCCCGCUGGCCACCAGCCAUCAGGCAGGCCACACGCUGGAAGUACACGCCCAUGGGACGGGACGCAGCCGGCCAGCUGUGGUACACAGGCCUGACCAACUCGGACGCCUGGGAAGCCUGGUACAACCUGCCACGGGCCCCGGCCAGCCCCUUCCGCGAGGCCUACAACCGCUGGCACAGCUGCUACCAACACCGUGAGUGCAGCAUGCCAUCGGCCUACACCCAGCACCUGCGGGAGACCGCCUGGCAUGACCCCAUCGUCCCUGCCCAGUACCAGGCCCCCAGCACCCGGUGGGGGAGCGCGCUGUGGAAAGACAGGCCAAUCCGGGGCAAGGAAUACGUGCUCAACAGGAACCGGUACGGGGUGGAGCCACUGUGGAGGGCAUCAGACUACGUGCCCUCCCUGUCGGCACCCCAGCGCCCGCCCGGCACCACCCAGAACUACCGGGAGUGGGUCCUGGAACCAUACUGCCCCUCCACCUGCCAGCGGUCCCCGCCUUCCCUCACACCCACUCCCCGAUAAAGGCAUGCUACCAGGAUGCA